CUCUGCGCCAACCCCGCGCGCCACCCGCGGCUUCCUCCGCUCGGGGUCCUCGUUCGGCCUCUGCUGGCCUCCGCGACUCCGCGGUGCCCGCCCCCGUUGAGUUCAAAAGGACGCGCGGAGCGGCGCCGGCCCUUCACCAGCAGCCCGUCCGACUGGAAAGAUCUGCCUCUUCUCCAAGAAACUCAACCACUAGUGACAAUGACCAGCCUCCUGACUACUCCUUCUCCAAGAGAAGAACUGAUGACCACCCCAAUUUUACAGCCCACUGAGGCCCUGUCCCCAGAAGAUGGAGCCAGCACAGCACUCAUUGCAGUUGUUAUCACCGUUGUCUUCCUCACCCUGCUCUCGGUCGUGAUCUUGAUCUUCUUUUACCUGUACAAGAACAAAGGCAGCUACGUCACCUAUGAACCUACAGAAGGUGAGCCCAGUGCCAUCGUCCAGAUGGAGAGUGACUUGGCCAAGGGCAGCGAGAAAGAGGAAUAUUUCAUCUAAUGACUCCCAGGCCCCAAGGAGCUUAUUCCUGGCUCCAUCGCUAACACGUUGACUGCUUAUUAUGGGAAAGUUUUCUCUGAAGCCAGGGAGAAGCAUUGAUUGAUGUGGGCAAAUCCAAGCUCCAGCCAGGUCGCAGUCCCAAAUGCCGACAUCACUGACUCCAGGGACCAGGGACAUGGAGAAAGCUGUUUAUGAUAUCUUUAACCAGGCCCUCUUACUAGAGCUGGUGUUUGUGACUGGCCAACAAGAUGUGGCUAUGCCAGGGGACAUCUGAGUAUGUGCCCAGUCAUCUUUUUUCACAGGUUGAAGGGAGAGAAAAGAUUUUGAGUUAAGGUCAUUGGCUGCUCUACUCUGUCCCCUACCUGGUCACCUAGUGAUAGCCCCAGUGGAGAUACUGUCCAUACAAGGUCUUCCCAGAGGCUGGAUACCACAGUAAAAGGCCAGGCCAGGAGGGGUAGGAGACUAUGGAGAUCUUACCUCCUGAUAAAUGUGCUACACCCCCUAAUCUGAGCCCUUCCUUUCCGUGUUCCCCAACAACCUCAUGCUUACGUGAUUUUUAUUCAAAUUAAAAAUUUUCAUUGCUACAGAAAUCAGAUUCUCAUGUGCAAGAAGUAACUACAUUUUGACUUAUUUUUGCUUAAACAUUUUUGACAUUUUCUUUUCCCUAUUUAACGCCUUUACAUAUGUUCUCUUCCAAGCAAUAAGAACCCUAGGAAAGUUCUAGAAGUUUGCAGAACUAUCUCAGGGAUUUGAGACAAAGAUGGUGCAGGAAAGCUUGUUCCAGGGGAACAUCAUUAGAAACAUACCCUGGGAGGGCCGGGUUCGGUGGCUCACGCCUGUGAUCCCAGCACUUUGGGAGGCCGAGGCAGGCGGAUCACAAGGUUAGGAGAUCGAGACCAUCCUGGCUAACACGGUGAAACCCCGUCUCUACUAAAAAUAUAUAAAAAAAAUAGCUGGGCGUGGUGGCGGGCGCCCAUAGUCCCAGCUGCUUGGGAGGCUGAGGCAGGAGAAUGGCUUGAACCCAGGAGGCGGAGCUUGCAGUGAGCUGAGAUUGCACCACUAUACUCCAGCCUGGGCAACAGAGUGAGACUCCGUCUCAAAAAAAAAAAAAAAAAAAAAAGUACCCUGGGAGAUGAGUUGGUUCAAGCCUCCAUCCUGGCAAGGGCCAGAAUUUCCCAGAAUCCCUUCUACAUAUAUACAGAAGGAACCAGAAAAAAUCAACCUACCACCUUUCCCAGUGUAUCCUCAGAAUCAAGCCAAGAAGCUUCUUGGAUUUUAGUCUCAAGAUAAGUUGUGUUUAAAAGGCACAUUUUGGUAUAAAUUAUUAGCUCAUCAGAUAUUGUUCACUUUGGAAUUAAAGCUAGAUCUCCUUUGAAGUCUUAA